AUUGUGUCAGAGGAAGCAACCAUGCAGGUGCUAACCAAGCGUUACCCCAAGAACUGCCUGCUGACCGUCAUGGACCGGUAUGCAGCCGAGGUGCACAACAUGGAGCAGGUGGUGAUGAUCCCCAGCCUUCUGCGGGACGUGCAGCUGAGUGGGCCUGGGGGCCAGGCCCAGGCUGAGGCCCCUGAUCUCUACACCUACUUCACCAUGCUCAAGGCCAUCUGUGUGGAUGUGGACCAUGGGCUGCUGCCGCGGGAGGAGUGGCAGGCCAAGGUGGCAGGCAGCGAAGAGAAUGGAACCGCAGAGACAGAGGAAGUCGAGGACGAGAGUGCCUCAGGAGAGCUGGACCUGGAAGCCCAGUUCCACCUGCACUUCUCCAGCCUCCAUCACAUCCUCAUGCACCUCACCGAGAAAGCCCAGGAGGUGACAAGGAAAUACCAGGAAAUGACGGGACAAGUUUGGUAGACCUUGGACACUAGGGAAGAUCCCUUCACAUGAUAGAAGACAGACUCUUUGAUGAGGUCGGCGGAGCAGUUCACUAGCCAAUGAUGAGAGCAGAAAGGCCUAGACCUGCAGCCAGAAGUGAAGGCGGCUCAGUUCUCCGGGAUGCUUCUCUACCUCCUGAGCACCAAUUCCUGGAUUCCAGUCACUGGCUCACCUUUAGAAUGUCUGUUGCUAUUCACUGCUCCCCUCGCUCCUCUUAACAGCUUGGGGAGGUGACCAGUGGUUCAGGAGGGACUAGACAAUUACCUGUCCAGUGUGGUAUGGUAGGAAGAGUGUAGGUGUUGGCACGUGACCAAAAUUCACAUCCCUCCUCAUGGCAGUCAUUCAGUAUGUGUACUUGUACAAGUUAUUUAACCCAUUGGAGCCUAAAUUCCCUCAUCUAUAAAAUGGGGAUAAUAUUAUCUACCUCACAAGCUUAUGAAAACUAAACAUGAUGAAUCAAAAGCACUUGGCAUGUGAGGGCUAUUAAAAUAGCCUGAUUUUUUUUUUCUCCCCCUCUCCCCAAUGUAUUUGCUCUGGCCCUUGCUUUUUACCCUCCAGAGCUAAGAGGUAGCAGAGUCUCUUGGGAUGAGUGAUUCACCCUCUUACUUGGCGACCACUGAUGAGAUCAACAACAGGUGAACUAUAAACCUAUUAUUUAUUGCAGAACUAAUAAAAAAUCCAAAGCCUUGUA